UGGGCAACAGAGUGAGACUCCAUCUCAAAAAAAAAAAAGAAAUGAAAACUGAGGGGACACAGGGGACCUGAGGGUGGACAGCACAGGAAGGGACGGCUUGCCCCUCUCAGCCACCCCCAUGGGGCCCUGGUGUUGGGUCACACACGGAUCCUGUCUGGAAUAGGAGUUGUCCUGGGCGCUGGGGCCCCAGGGGCCAGGCUGCCAUGAAUCCUCAGGCCCGGCUCUGGAACAGGGUGUAUUUGAAGAGUGUCACUGGAAAGGCCAGGGUCGGAGCCGUCUGUCCCCUGCCAGGCAGCUGGCAGGAGCCCUGGCCGGGCCUUGUGUGUCAGCAAUCUCAGACAGGGUGAGGAUGACAAGGUUUUCCAUGGCCGGGGCCCGAGCUCAGAGGGGCAUGCGUCAGGGCCUGGGCCGAGUCCAGCAGACUCUGGUCUUGGAUGGAACUGGUUGCAAUCCUGCCUCUGACAGGGAGGUGGAGGCACGGGUGCUGGCAGACCCUCCAACACACAGGCACAGACACACGGGGCAGGGGGCUCCAUCCCAACAGGAGGAUCCCAGGCUGAGGCCGCACUCCACCCAGCGUACCUGUCCUCGGUGCAGAUGUGGGCGCUGCCCCUGAGGAGCUUUGGUUUCUAAGGGGAGAGCUGGCCAAGUCAUCAACACUGGACGGACAGCAGGAAAGGCGUGAGGACAGCGGCUCUCGAGGGAGGAGGAGCAGCCCGGCAGCCCUCCCGGAAACAGUGGCACCGUGUUCGCAGGGGGAACAGCGUCCAGGGACCACGCACACCCACGAAGAUGAAGAAGCCUGUGCCUCCUCGCAUCGCGCUUACAGGGAAAUUCCUUGUGGGUCCCAAGAUCUUGGCUCUGAAACAGUUCUGCUGGAUCCCACCCAGAUAGUGUGAUCUAGCAGCUUAUCUUCCCAGAUCGAGUGUUCAUGCAGUGUGGCGUUCGUGCCGUGUGGAUGCUGCUGAGGUGUGAACCCUGUCACAGACCAAGGCUCCAGUGAGCCACAGCGUGGCCAGGCGGAAGCAGAAGAGACCGGUGACCCCCACUCAACUCAGCCUCUCCUUCCUCCAGGGAGAGUGUCCUGGAGGUACCUGUCCGAGUGACAGGGAAGGGGCGGGGCCGGGAGCCAAGGCUGGAAGCUCAGCCCCACUCAGCCUUUGCAAAUGCUCUAGUGGGAGCAGCUGGCCUCAGGGGAGGGCUUAAAACUCCAGGAGAGCCUGGGCAGGUGCGGACGCGAGGGGAGUGGAGGGGAGGCCUCGCCUGGCCCACCUUCCUCCUGCCCCUCUACCAUGUGGCCCUUCCCGAGCCGCUCUCUCUUCCCACCCCCGACUCAGGCCUGGCUCCAGACGGUCUCCUCAGACCCUGAGGCCCAGGGCUGGGGGGCCUGGAACGAGACCAAGGAGAUUCUGGGGCCAGAGGGUGGGGAAGGGAAGGAGGAGAAAGAGGAGGAAGAGGAUGCAGAGGAAGACCAGGAUGGGGAUGCAGGCUUUCUGCUGUCUCUGCUGGAGCAAGAGAACCUGGCUGAGUGCCCAUUGCCUGACCAGGAGCUGGAGGCCAUCAAGAUGAAGGUGUGUGCCAUGGAGCAGGCCGAGGGGACGCCACGGCCUCCAGGAGUGCAGCAACAGGCCGAGGAAGAGGAGGGCACCGCGGCCGGGCAGCUGCUGAGCCCUGAGACCGUGGGCUGCCCCCUCUCUGGGACCCCCGAGGAGAAGGUGGAGGCUGACCACAGAUCCGUCUACGUGGGCAACGUGGACUACGGGGGCUCCGCCGAGGAGCUGGAGGCCCACUUCAGCCGCUGUGGGGAGGUCCACCGAGUCACGAUCCUGUGUGACAAGUUCUCUGGACACCCCAAGGGUUAUGCCUACAUAGAGUUUGCCACCAAGGGCUCCGUGCAGGCCGCCGUGGAGCUGGACCAGAGCCUCUUCCGGGGCCGGGUCAUCAAGGUGCUGCCGAAAAGAACCAACUUCCCUGGGAUCAGCUCCACAGACCGCGGGGGCCUUCGAGGACACCCAGGCUCCAGGGGGGCACCCUUCCCCCACAGCGGCCUCCAGGGCAGGCCCCGGCUCAGACCACAAGGGCAGAACCGGGCCCGUGGAAAAUUCUCACCAUGGUUUUCACCGUAUUAAAGGGAAGACCCGAUUUUGAGAGAGGGGCUGGGGCCUGGAUCAGGAGUAAACCACUUGUGCUCCAUCCUGGGGCUGGGGCAGGGAGUGGCGCGGGGGCGAGGCCAGAGGAGAGGGGUGUCCAGAGCAGCCACUGGCCCCCUCUUGGCGGGGGGAUGGCCCAGUAGGGCCUUGUAUGGUGGUCCAGACCCAAGGCCACAGCCACGAGUCACAGCCACGGCCCGGUGGUGAGCCUGGCAUGGGCCCCACGGGGAUCUGCGGGGCUCUGGGUGUUGAGGGAGGGGAGGAGCAGAGUCCCAGGCAGUGCCAGGCCAGCUUGGGGUUGGCAUGCUCAGCUCUUCAACUAAGUCAUUUUAAGAAAAAUAGAAACGUGUGUCUUAAUGGUGAAGCAUAAAUUAUUAAACUUGGGCUCUUUUUAAAAGCAAA